AACCAGUAGCCCUGGAGCUGCUCUGCCUAUGGAGUAGCCAUCCUUUUACUUCUUUGCUUUCUUAAUAAACUUGUUUUCACUUUACUCUAUGGGCUUGCCCUGAAUUCUUUCUUGCAUGAGAUCCAAGAACCCUCUCUUAGGGCCUGGAUCGGGACCCCUUUCUGAUAACACCAGGAGACACCCUGGGUGGAUUUCCUGAACCGACCGAUAGAUGAGCCUUCCACGCGGGAGACCUGGAUCCUUAUCGUCUUUGUGGCCCCUUCCAUCUGCACGUGCGGACGAGGUCCGGGUCGCACUCGGGCGGUCAGCCUGGCACGCACAGCGCCGGCGUGCAGGGGGCCUUGGGUGCCACCGAGUCCGGGAGGAAAUCUAGGCCGCCAUCCGUCCGGAGACUGGCACCUGUGACCACCACCCAACAUGUAUUGAACAAGGGCUUGGAGGUCCUUUCUCUAAGGCCGCACCGAUAAACGAUUACCGACUGUUGACCUCACGGCCCCUUCGCUUCCGGCCGCACCGCCUCGCUGCCCACGCCUGCGCACUCAGGCACCGCAGAUUCAUUUGGAUUCAAGGUUGGCUCUCAACAGUGCCAGCUGCACUGUCAUCCUAAAGUACUUCUGUGGAAGAGAACAUGGUGGUGUCACUGUUGUACCAGUGAUGACACAAAAUCCCAGAUCUACCUGACGGGCCUGCGAGGGUUGAAGAUUGUGAAGCAAUAGCCUAAGGGACUGGCUGGCUUCGAGCAGGGCAUCGGAACCAGGCCUCCUGGCACUGGCCUGGGUAGAGCCAGGGCGAGCACCAGCUGACCCCCAGUGGAACCCUGUGACAGUCCUGCCAGGGCCCAGGCCAUCCCAACCGACUUCCAUCUCAUGGACCCUCCAGCGGAGAAGCCGGGAGAGGCUGGCGGACUGCAGAUCACACCCCAGCUGCUGAAGUCACGCACAGGCGAGUUCUCCCUGGAGUCCAUCCUGCUACUGAAGCUGCGUGGCUUGGGACUGGCUGACCUGGGCUGCCUGGGAGAGUGCCUGGGCCUGGAGUGGCUGGACCUAUCAGGCAACGCGCUCACCCACCUGGGCCCGCUGGCCUCCUUGCGCCAGCUAGCUGUGCUCAAUGUCUCCAACAAUCGGCUGACGGGCCUGGAGCCACUGGCCACCUGUGAGAACUUGCAGAGUCUCAAUGCCGCAGGCAACCUACUGGCCACCCCGGGCCAGCUGCAGUGUCUGGCUGGGCUACCGUGCCUGGAGUACCUGCGGCUCCGAGACCCUUUGGCCCGGCUCAGCAACCCGCUCUGUGCCAACCCCUCCUACUGGGCUGCAGUCCGGGAGCUGCUGCCUGGCCUGAAAGUCAUCGACGGUGAGCGUGUGAUUGGGCGUGGUAGUGAGUUCUACCAGCUGUGCCGAGACCUGGACAGCUCCUUGCGUCCCAGCUCCAGUCCAGGCCCCAGAGCCACCGAGGCCCAGCCCUGGGUGGAGCCAGGCUACUGGGAGUCCUGGCCCAGCCGGAGCAGCUCCAUCCUGGAGGAGGCCUGCCGGCAGUUCCAGGACACACUGCAGGAGUGCUGGGACCUGGACCGCCAGGCCAGCGACAGCCUGGCCCAGGCGGAGCAGGUACUCAGCUCUGCGGGCCCCACCUCUUCCUUCGUCUUCUGAACGUGGCCUAUGGCCCAGGACAGCCUGGCAGGUGGCCUCGCUGCCCCCAGUUCCCCUCUCUGCCCCCACACUCGUCUUAGUUGCUUCACACUGGUCACUGGCCCUGCACACUGGGCUAUUGCUUUAUCCCUAUCCUGAGAGCAGCCCCUCCCCACCAUCCCUCCACAUGCUGCAAGGACAGACUGAAGGGCUGUGAGCAGGUGUAAGGGCUCCCACAUCCGUGAGCCUGUGUCCGCAGCUGCUGCCACUCUGGGCUGCUCCAGCCUGCAACUUAGUGGAAGGAAUUACUUCCUCCUGAGGCUACAGGCGAGAAAGGUAGGGAUGGGCCAGCCUCCCGUCUCAGCUGUUGGGAGACAGUAGGCAGGCUGAGUGGCCCAGAGCACUCCUGGAAGUGGGACUCCCCUGCCUUGCAAAUGUGCCUCUCCAGACUGCUCCUGCACUUACCCCCUCCCCGCAGCACCUUCUCUGCCCGUUCUUGUCCACACAUCUAUUAAAUGCUUCUGUUUUCAUUUGCA